AAUCUGGCCCCCACCUUUUCUUGGGCUUGUAGGAAGGUGGACAUGGGCUCCCGGAGACAAGACAAGUGAUAUGUUGAACUGUUCGGUGGCUGGAAUCAACUGCUCCUGGAGUGACCUAAGGCCAGUGUUUAUCAGAACUUAGCCAGGGCCAGCCAAGCAGGCACAGAUGCUCUGCUAUGAAAUGCCACGCAGGCAGAGACUGACAAGCGGUAGGAACUGAGCUUUCCCCUUGGACUGCUGCUUCCUGCUGUGUUCAGGGGAGGGGGUCACUUUCUGGCAACUCUGCUGCUGCUGCUGCUGCUGCUGCUACUUCAGCUUCCUCUCCACUCAAGGUAAGCAGGCUAAGGGAGGGCAGGCUGCUAGGGAAAGCUUUGUACCAUGAACAGGAUCCGAAAGUUUUUCCGAGGAAGUGGGCGAGUCUUGGCAUUUAUCUUUGUAGCUUCUGUCAUCUGGCUCCUCUUUGACAUGGCAGCUCUCCGCCUCUCAUUCAGUGAGAUCAACACUCGGGUCAUCAAGGAAGACAUUGUGAGGAGGGAGCGGAUAGGAUUCAGAGUUCAGCCAGACCAAGGAAAAAUUUUUUACAGCAGCAUAAAAGAGAUGAAACCUCCCCUAAGGGGACAUGGGAAAGGGGCAUGGGGCAAAGAGAAUGUUAGAAAAACUGAGGAGAGUGUGCUCAAGGUUGAGGUGGACUUGGACCAAACCCAGAGGGAAAGAAAAAUGCAGAAUGCCCUGGGAAGGGGCAAGGUUGUGCCGUUGUGGCAUCCUGCACAUCUGCAGACCCUCCCUGUGACUCCUAACAAGCAGAAGACAGACGGGAGAGGCACCAAACCUGAAGCCUCCUCUCACCAGGGGACACCAAAGCAAACGACAGCUCAGGGGGCUCCAAAGACCUCAUUCAUAGCAGCAAAAGGAACUCAGGUAGUCAAAAUAUCAGUACACAUGGGACGUGUCAGUUUAAAACAGGAGCCCCGGAAGAGUCAUAGUCCCAGCAGUGACACAUCAAAACUAGCAGCUGAAAGGGACUUGAAUGUGACCAUCAGUCUUAGUACUGAUAGACCAAAGCAGCGAUCACAGGCAGUAGCAAACGAGAGGGCACACCCUGCCAGCACAGCAGUGCCGAAGUCUGGGGAAGCCAUGGCCUUAAACAAAACUAAGACUCAGAGCAAAGAAGUCAAUGCAAAUAAACACAAAGCCAAUACGAGUCUUCCUUUUCCUAAGUUCACUGUCAAUUCAAAUCGCUUAAGGAAGCAAUCUAUUAAUGAGACACCUUUGGGAAGUUUGUCAAAGGAUGAUGGAGCUAGAGGGGCUCAUGGGAAGAAACUCAAUUUCUCUGAAAGCCAUCUUGUGAUUAUAACCAAAGAGGAAGAGCAAAAGGCAGACCCCAAAGAGGUCUCUAAUUCUAAAACCAAAACAAUAUUUCCUAAAGUAUUGGGUAAAAGCCAAAGUAAACACAUUUCCAGGAAUAGAAGUGAGAUGUCUUCCUCUUCACUUGCUCCACAUAGAGUGCCACUGUCCCAAACUAACCAUGCUUUAACUGGAGGGCUAGAGCCAGCAAAAAUCAACAUAACUGCCAAAGCCCCCUCUACAGAAUACAACCAGAGUCAUAUAAAAGCCCUUUUACCUGAAGACAGUGGAACGCACCAGGUGUUAAGAAUUGAUGUGACACUUUCUCCAAGGGACCCCAAAGCUCCAGGGCAGUUUGGGCGUCCUGUAGUUGUCCCCCAUGGAAAGGAGAAGGAGGCAGAAAGAAGAUGGAAAGAAGGAAACUUCAAUGUCUACCUUAGCGAUUUGAUCCCAGUGGAUAGAGCCAUUGAAGACACCAGACCUGCUGGGUGACAGCUUUUCCUUCCUUUGUUUCCUUAUAGUCAUAUGACAUUGGCAGAAAUUAAAACACCUCUCUUCCUUAUACAUGGAUGUGCAGAGCAGCUAGUUCACAAUAACCUCCCAACCACCAGUGUCAUCAUGUGCUUUGUGGAUGAAGUGUGGUCCACUCUCCUGAGAUCUGUUCACAGUGUCAUCAAUCGCUCUCCUCCACACCUCAUCAAGGAGAUUCUGCUGGUAGAUGACUUCAGCACCAAAGACUAUCUAAAAGAUAAUUUGGAUAAAUACAUGUCCCAGUUUCCAAAAGUUCGGAUUCUUCGCCUCAAAGAGAGACAUGGCUUAAUAAGGGCCAGGCUGGCAGGAGCACAGAAUGCAACAGGUGAUGUGUUGACAUUUUUAGAUUCUCAUGUGGAAUGUAACGUUGGUUGGUUGGAACCUCUUCUGGAAAGAGUUUAUUUAAGUAGAAAGAAAGUGGCCUGUCCAGUAAUCGAAGUCAUCAAUGAUAAGGAUAUGAGUUACAUGACAGUGGAUAACUUUCAAAGAGGCAUCUUUGUGUGGCCCAUGAACUUUGGUUGGAGAACAAUUCCUCCAGAUGUCAUUGCAAAAAACAGAAUUAAAGAAACUGAUACAAUAAGGUGCCCUGUCAUGGCUGGUGGAUUGUUUUCUAUUGACAAAAGUUACUUUUUUGAACUUGGAACAUACGACCCUGGCCUUGAUGUUUGGGGUGGGGAAAAUAUGGAGCUCUCAUUCAAGGUGUGGAUGUGUGGUGGUGAAAUUGAGAUCAUUCCCUGCUCCCGAGUGGGCCAUAUAUUCAGAAAUGACAAUCCAUAUUCCUUCCCCAAAGACCGGAUGAAGACAGUGGAGCGGAACUUGGUGCGGGUUGCCGAGGUCUGGCUGGAUGAGUAUAAGGAGCUGUUCUAUGGCCACGGAGACCACCUCAUCGACCAAGGGCUAGAUGUUGGCAACCUCACCCAGCAAAGGGAGCUGCGAAAGAAACUGAAGUGCAAAAGUUUCAAAUGGUACUUGGAGAAUGUCUUUCCUGACUUAAGGGCUCCCAUUGUGAGAGCUAGUGGUGUGCUUAUUAAUGUGGCUUUGGGUAAAUGCAUUUCCAUUGAAAACACUACAGUCAUUCUGGAAGACUGCGAUGGGAGCAAAGAGCUUCAACAAUUUAAUUACACCUGGUUAAGACUUAUUAAAUGUGGAGAAUGGUGUAUAGCCCCCAUCCCUGAUAAAGGAGCCGUAAGGCUGCACCCUUGUGAUAACAGAAACAAAGGGCUAAAAUGGCUGCAUAAAUCAACAUCAGUCUUUCAUCCAGAACUGGUGAAUCACAUUGUUUUUGAAAACAAUCAGCAAUUAUUAUGCUUGGAAGGAAAUUUUUCUCAAAAGAUCCUGAAAGUAGCUGCCUGUGACCCAGUGAAGCCAUAUCAAAAGUGGAAAUUUGAAAAAUAUUAUGAAGCCUGAAGUGUAACUGAUGUUUUUAUAUAGUAAACCCAUUAAAUACUGUGAAAAUAACACUGAACUUGGAAACUAUAUUUCUCAGCGGUAGUUUAAAUUUUCAAUUUUAAUAACAUUUGAAUGGAAGAUUUUUUAUAAAUCACAAUAUUUGGAAUACCAAAAGAUGACUCAGGAAAACAGUCCAACAUUGGACUGAAGUCCUUCUUCGGAACUGGGUGGCCUUUGAAUUGCCUGCUUUCCACCCUAUGCUAGACCUCAUCAUGCAAAUUUCCCUGUGAAAGCUAACAGGUAACUGGAAAUGAAGACAGAAGGACUUGAGAAAGCAUGAGGAUAUUCCCAAUGACUAUGUUUGGUAAUAAUCAGCUCUUCUGGCCCACAAGUAGGAAUGAUCAAUGAGAACUUAACUUAGUCCUUUAUUUGGGGAUUUUUUCAUCAAACAAAAAUUUCUUGAGUUCUUAUGGCUAGAAGACCUCAGAUGCCCACAGCUGUCACGUUUGUGAAAUCCCUCCAGACUACAUGCAUGCUUACCUAACAGUUUGAAAUAGUAUUGAUCUACUGCUGGUAACCCUGCUUGAUGGCAGCAUUUUGAUCUAAAUUACAUAAUGGUUUUUCCCAAUCUGAAUCAGUGGAAAAAAAUUUAAGUGAGGAAGAAGAGGCCUUCAAAUGCUUAUUUAAUUCUAGGUAUGAACACUAUUUCAGUUCAUUUUGUGCUUUUAAAACUACAGUUUUAAAGAUUUAUGAUACCAAUAACUUCCUAGAUUCAUGUGGAUUUUUUUUAAGGCAAUGAAAAAAGGCUGGAUUAUAACACACUGUAGUAAUCAAAAAUGCAUUUAAGCAUUGAAUGCACUCUAGUGCAGGGCCAAGUAAGAGGAGUUGAAAUGAGUAAAGCAGAAAUAGAGCUGCUGAAAGUUUCUUUUAUAUAAAAAUAAUAAAAUACUACUUUAGAUAUAGUAGCAUUCACAGGGAUGAAAUAUGCGAAAAAUGGGUUCUAAAAUAUUUCAAAGGGAAAAUGAAGUGAAGGAAACAUCAUGAAAGGGGAAAGGAAUGAGGUAAACAAGUCUUAGGAAGAGAGUUAAGAAAAAAUUCCGCUGGACUUGGCCAAAGAAAGAAGGGGAUCUAGUAUCUCUAUGAAGGAAAAAAGAGUAAAGCCCUCAGUGUGAACCCAGUGAGAACACUGACAAAUUUGGGAAAAGUUAAAUACUGAUUUCAUCCAAAUAAAGCCUCUAAUCUUAAGCAUACCAAUACUUUGGCAUACCAGAAGACACCUUAGAAAUCAGGAUAGCCUUUGCAUUCAUUUUGGUAAGAAAACUGAUGCUGAGAGGAUAAAUUACCUAAAAAUCUUAAAACCCAGGCAAGUUAGUCAAAGAAUCAAGAUUAGAAUUCAGGUUUCCAGAGACAGGGCUCAUUCUAAUGCCUCAGGUCACUGGCCCGAACAAAUCUGCUUCACAGAAUUCCUUAGAAAGAGAUACACAAUUCUUUGCUGGGAUUGGGUCCCUGGAGGACAACCAUACUAUAUUCUUGUUAAUAUGUUUUUUCUUUUUUUAAAUUUAAACUUUUGUUCAGUUGAGAUGAUUGUGAAACUAGGUAUCUUUCAUUCUGACUCCUAGUUUAACAUUUAAUUUUGACUCCCAAUGAGUUACGUAAAAGCAAAACUAUAACUAAGAAUGGGAAAAAGAACUAUUUCUGCACAUUUGUAACAUAUUUAAGAUGUUUUCUUCAUAUAAUUGAAAACUGCAGAUGAGUAAGAGAAUGACUAGGAAAUGAGAUACAGUUAUAUGACACAUAAUGAUGUUUUAGUCAACAAUGAACCACAUAUUUGACAUUGGUCCCAAAAGAUUAUAUUAAUAAUAUGGUAUCUUUAGUGUGCUUUUCUAUGUUUAGACACACAAAUACUCACCAUGAUGUUACAAUAGCCUACAGUGUUCAAUACAGUAACAUGCACAAGUUUGUAACCUAGGAGCAACAGGGAUUCCAUAUAGCCUAGGUGUGUAGUAGGCUACCUACACCAUCUAGGUUUGUGUAAGUACACUCUGAUAUUCACACAAUGAUGAAAUUGCCUAAUGACACAUUUCUCAGAAUGUAUUUGUGUUAUUAAAUGAUGCAUGACUCUAAUUCUUUUCAAAACAGAGCCAUAUGGGGCAAGGGGGAUGGGGGGACGCAAGUCAGUUGUCAAAAGACUAAUUGAGUUACUGACAAACUGAACAUGCUAGGUGCCUCAUGUAAUUCUUCAUGUAACUAAAAAAUGUUGAGAGGUUUUUUUCCCCCGGGUAUAUAGGCUCUCUUUUUAUCCGAAAAUAGUUUCCACAAAGAAGUCAACUCUGUUCUGAAAAAAAAUGAAUUGCAUUUUGAAUACACUUAUCUUUGGGUAUAUCAACUAAAGGAAGUUGGAUUUUUUUCCUUAACAGAAACUUCUGCAGUCCUCUCAGUUCACAUCCUUUCUGACUUUACCCUGACAAACUUAUUAUAUAAAGCUAUAUUUAAAUCUAUAUUGUCAAUAUAACAAAGGAUUGUUUUUGAACAUCACAAAUUUGUUCUUGGAUAGAAUUUUAUACAUUGCUUUUCAUCAUAUAUUUGCUCAGUUACUCUAAGAAGCAAGGAACUGAUCACUAGUUGGGAAUCUAUAUGGGCCUAAACUUGAGUGUAUUGAUUUAUUAUUACAUCUACUACCAACAUUUUCUUAAGCAUAGCCUUCUAAAUUUUUUCAGGAGAUUAGAAUAAAGGUAUACAUGCUACUCGGUCUUCUGGUAAUUCUAGUGAUAAACCUUUGGAUGAGACAGGUCCUAAUCAGCACUGAAUUCUUCAAUAGGAGGCUGUGUUACAGGAGCUACAGAUUUUUCCCUGGAUUAGCUUAGGUCAUUGCCUUUACUUUAAAAAAAAAAAAAAAAAGUCUAUGCAUCUUGUUACCUUGAAUACAAGGGUGGUCUUGAUAAUAUUUGACAGCACUAACCAACUUACCAAGCCAUCUAAGUGCUUCUGAGACUUUUCAGUUUGCACAAUUUCUUUCUCCUUUUCAACAGUUACCCAGCGCUUCUGCCCUACUCUCUUGUAAGCUGACACAGUUGUUGUUGGUACAAUCUUGUUCUAUCACCAGCAUCAAAUUUGCUUAAUACUGCUUGUUGACAUCCCCUCAGCUGUCAUUCACAGCAAACCACCAUGUGCCAUGAUCACAAUGUAUUAUUAGCUUCGCCACACUAAUUUGGAAACAUUCUUUUAGAUAUUAAAACACCUUACUUCUAGUAUUAGUUUGGGACUGCAGAGGGGCAAAGAUACCAUUUACAGUAUAUAGGAGUCCAAUAUUCCCAACCAACCUUGAUUUCAUGAAUGGCUUGUAAUUAUUUCUAGCAGGCACUCAUGCAAUAGAAUAAGAUUGAAACAUGCCAGAGAGUACCAUCUUUCUUUGUUUUAACAUCUCUGAUUGAAUUCCUAUAUUCAGAAUACAAGAAAAAAAAUUUACCAACCAGGCGCAGUGGCUCACACCUGUAAUCCUAGCACUUUAGGAGGCCAAGGUGGGUGGAUCAUGAGGUCAGGAGUUCAAGACCAGCCUGGGCAACAUGGUGAAACCCCGUCUCUACUAAAAAUACAAAAAUUAGCUGGGCAUGGUGGUGGGCGCCUGUAAUCCCAGCUACCUGGGAGGCUGAAGCAGGAGAAUUGCUUGUACCCGGGAGGUGGAGGUUGCAGUGAGCUGAAAUUGCGCCACUGCACUCCAGCCUAGACAACAGAGCAAGACUCUAUCUCAAAAAAUAAUAAUAAUAAUUUUUACCUCAGAAGAAAGCCCCAAAAUCUUGGAUUAAAACAAAAAAAUGACAUUGGGUGAUGGGAAAAAAGAAAGGAACUAAUUAUCAUUGAGUGUGUGUAGGUACUAUUUGUGUAGGUGCUAUAUGUGUCCCAUCUCACUGAUGGGUACAACUCAUCAAAUGACUCUCAUUCUCCCUGUUAUAUGAACAAGAAGGAUAACUCCCACAUACAGAUGAGGAAUUUGGUAAAUUGCCCAAGGUCAUCCCACAAGUAAGAGAUAAAACCCAGUUUCCAUUUUAUCUGGCUCAAAAAAAAUUUCUCUCACUAUACCAUGCUGCUAUAUAAUUAAUUUUCUUCUUUACAAAGGGCUGUCAUCUCAGGUGGGUGCAUUUAAAAGUUUCUUGGUCUCAGAUUACUGAUGCCACAGUAUUGAGAUGAGAUUGAAUUAAACCCCUUUGGCCUCUUUUGGAUGUUGUAUAAACAGAAAAAAGAAGCAUGGUCUCUCUCUCUCUGUGGUAACCAAUUGAUGUGUAGGUAUAAACAUGGCUACCCCCACAUGUUUUGCUGUGAUCUAUCUCUUUGACUUCAUGCAGAACCUAUUCUUUUUCAUCUCCUGGACCAAAUGUGAAAGAAAGAAGUGGACAUGUGGAGGAUUCUUUCUCUGUGAAUAAUAUUGAAAAAGCUCCAUUUUCUGGGGAAAUACCCAUGGUUCAUUGUCUGAUGCCAAGAAAGAAUUCAGGACACAGACACACAUGAGGAGUGGGUUUAGGAGUGGAAAGUUUAAUAGAUAAAGAAGAGAGUGAGAAAGCUUCCUCAUGUUGAGAAAGACAGUUGCUCAAGAGAGGGUUUUCUGGGUUUGGGGCAAGAUUUGAUUGAUUUCAUACAGAGGCUUGAGGAGGCGGUGAUUGAUAUACAUAGGGCCCGGGGAUUGGUUUAACCAGGUAUACUACUUACAUAGCCGGUGAAAAGACUGGCCCUCCCACCCUAACCUUUUAUUAUGCAAAUGCAUCUUCUACCUGGCUGUCACCAUGACAUUUGCACACGUGGCUUCACUUCACCAGUGCCAUGUCACCCACACACCUGGUGACAAGGAAAAGGGAGCAGGAAUCACCAUAUUGAAUGUGCCUGGCUUCCAGGUACAGCUGCUAGCUUUACAUAUGGGAGCCUCUAGCUUGCAUAUCUAUACUUGCAACUUGACUUUUCAGGCUGCUUUUUGUUAGAAAAUAAGUGGCUUGGGGGCUGCUUUUUAUUAAAGGAAAAAUCCACCGAGAACUAUUUUACCCUUUCUAAUGGCCUAAAAUAAAUUUUUAAUGACUCCUGUAUUAAUAUUACCAACCCUUGAUCCCUCCAACCUUUAAUCAAAGCUAGCAGAUUGCUCAUCUUGAACAGAAAUAAAAAGUUAAAAAGUUGGAGUCCUUUAAAACACAAACCAUGACUUUUUAUUCCUACUCAUUGUGUAGGUUGUCACUACUGUGCUUUUGCAACAACUUUUGCAUGGGUUACUCAAUAGUUGCUACAAGACAAAAUGCCUUACAAUUAGAAAAAAAAAUUAACCAGAGAUAUUGUACAAAAUAUUUAUUUUUUGACAGUUUUGAAUAAGCCAUAUAAAGUAUUAUAUAUCCCUAAUGAAGCUUAAUGGAUAGUAUUCCAGGUGUUGGUGGUGUCUGUAUCUCAAAGAAAGAAAAAAAUAACAUCACACUAAACAGAUUUAAUGCCUCUGUUUUCAACCUAAUGGAACAAUAGUUAUCAUUUCAAUUAGAGUCGCUUUGCAAGUUUAUGUGAAUCUUUGCUUUGUAAAAACACAUACAAAACACAAGGGAAAAUUCUCAUUUUCCAGCAAAUACAGCAACUUCUAAUAUGCUGUUUCUAAUAAUGAGUCACCAUCAAAUAAGUAAUAAAUAUUUUUUUCAAAAACAAGAGCUUUCUGUUUUAUUAUUGAUUGACAGAUAUUUACCAGUUUAAGGAUAUUGGUCAUAAGCAUCUAUAUAAUAAACCCUUUAUAUUAGAUGUUAAAUUAAAAUUUUUCAUAGCAUGAAUAGAUUUUUAAGUGACCACUCAAAAACAUAGCAAUUUUUGUAAAUAUACUGUAUGUGUGUGUAUAUAUAUAUAUAUAUAUAUAUAUUUUUUUUUUUGAUGCUUUGAUCUGGAAGAAAGAAAUAUCAAGAGUUUCUAUUCACAACAUAAAGAAAAUAAAAUGUUUUUAGAUAUUUUUAACUCUUUCAGGUGUAUAGCUUUGUCUGCAUCUGGCCUUCUGCACAAAAGUAUCUCAAGUGAACUUACACUCUGGAUACCAUUUUCCAAACUUGAAGGAGUAAUCAAGUUCUUAAUUAUCAGGGUGCUUGUUAUUUAGUUGAAGAUUACACACAUGUCUUCUGCUUCAAACAACUACCCCAAAUUUGCUAGUUUUAUACAUAUUAGCUUAAAAACAAGAGAAGCCAAAGAUUAAGUAAGUGAAUUGUGUUAAAGAUUGCCUGAAAACAUUUGCUAAGGGGAGAAUAAAACUAAAACUGUGGAGUAUAAAGGAUGUUGGAAUUAAACAUUUUUAAGUACUUUUUCUUUUGCAUCUGAUCGACUGAAGUUAUUAUAAAGAAGGAAUCAAGUAUGUAACUUUAAAUUCUAGGUAAACAUCCAAAUUACUUUCUAAAUUCAUUUCCAAAAUUCUCCUGUGCUGGCAGUUAGCUACUAGAGAUCAUCAUUUGAUUUUGUAGUUUGCCAUGUUCUGAGUGAGUUCAGCUGCUUACUACUACCCAUGUCAUUGUGUUUGUAUUGAUUGCCUGGCUCAGUUAUCUCAUGUUCUUCAUGAACUAUAUACACAUUUUCAUUGUCUUUAAACAAUACUGAGUUUUGAAGUUAAGUAGAAUAUUGUAGGGGUUAUCAGAAACCCAUAUUCAUUGUGGUAUGUUUCUGUCUGAUACUUUAAUAUUGGUAAAUAUAGUUUUUGACAUUGCAUUUUACAAUCCUAUUGUUUUUUAGAGUGAUGAAAGUUCAAGUUUUAAGAGAAGUGGUUGCCUUUCUCAUACUGUCAAACAUAUUUCUUCUUUAUUAUACUCUGGUGCUUUAUCCUUCUCCAUAAUUCUCUAUUAUUACUUAUUUUAAAUGUUUUCCCUAUCACAUUGAAAAACUUAAAUGUCCGUUCUCCAUUUGAAAAUAUGCCAAAAGUAUGAUCCCAUGUAAAUAUGCAGAAACGAUUGCUAUGAAAAUGUCAGCAUAGUUUAAAUGUAUUACUCUGAUGAUUACAGAGAUUUCUUCAAGUUGUUCGUGUUAAGAUGCAUCUUAAACAUGAUCUCAGUUCCUUAAAAAAUGAUAAAAAUUUUUCAUGUAUAUUACAUAUCUACCUACCAGAAAUCCUUUUUACAAUUUUAUAUACAAUCAUUUUAAGACCUUUUUGAAAUAAAUAAUGCAAAUGAACUAAAA